ACGCGUGCGCUUAGGCGCCGCUGAGCGCUGACUGGGUGCGAGUGGGGAAGCUGCUAACCCGACCCGGAUUGGCGCUGAGGUGGCCCGUGGGGCAGGGCAGAUGAUUCUGGACCAGAUGAAGCCUGAGGAGCCUUCCAGCUCUAAGAUAGCAGGAUAGGAGACUUCUAAGAUUGGAGCUGCAGAAGACUUGCCAGCCCACCAGCACAAUGUCAGGAAGCCAUACACCUGCCUGUGGCCCUUUCUCAGCCCUGACUCCGAGCAUAUGGCCCCAGGAGAUCUUGGCCAAGUACACGCAGAAGGAAGAGUCAGCAGAGCAACCAGAGUUCUACUACGAUGAGUUUGGUUUCCGUGUGUACAAGGAAGAAGGUGAUGAGCCUGGCUCCAGUCUGCUGGCGAACUCCCCUCUGAUGGAGGAUGCUCCACAGAGGCUGCGGUGGCAGGCCCACCUGGAGUUCACCCAUAACCACGAUGUGGGGGAUCUCACCUGGGACAAGAUUGCCGUCUCCCUACCCCGCUCUGAGAAGCUCCGCUCCCUGGUGCUGGCCGGCAUCCCACAUGGCAUGAGGCCACAGCUGUGGAUGCGGCUCUCUGGGGCCCUGCAGAAGAAGAGGAACUCUGAGCUGUCCUACCGCGAGAUUGUGAAGAACAGCUCCAACGAUGAGACCAUCGCUGCCAAGCAGAUCGAGAAGGACCUGCUCCGCACCAUGCCCAGCAACGCCUGCUUCGCCAGCAUGGGUAGCAUCGGGGUGCCCCGCCUGCGCAGGGUGCUCCGGGCCCUGGCCUGGCUCUACCCAGAGAUCGGCUACUGCCAGGGCACCGGCAUGGUGGCCGCCUGCCUCCUGCUGUUCCUGGAGGAGGAGGACGCCUUCUGGAUGAUGUCUGCCAUCAUCGAGGACCUGCUCCCCGCCUCCUACUUCAGCACCACCCUGCUGGGUGUCCAGACUGACCAGCGGGUCCUGCGCCACCUCAUUGUCCAGUACCUGCCUCGCCUGGACAAGCUGCUCCAGGAGCAUGACAUUGAGCUGUCCCUGAUCACACUGCACUGGUUCCUCACGGCCUUCGCCAGCGUGGUGGACAUCAAGCUGCUCCUGCGCAUCUGGGACCUGUUUUUCUACGAGGGCUCCCGGGUGCUGUUCCAGCUCACGCUGGGCAUGCUGCACCUCAAGGAGGAAGAGCUGAUCCAGUCAGAGAACUCGGCCUCCAUCUUCAACACGCUAUCGGAUAUCCCGUCGCAGAUGGAGGACGCGGAGCUGCUUCUGGGGGUGGCCAUGCGGCUGGCCGGCUCCCUCACCGAUGUGGCCGUGGAGACUCAGCGCCGCAAGCACCUGGCCUAUCUCAUUGCAGACCAGGGCCAGCUCCUGGGGGCCGGCACCCUCACCAACCUCUCUCAGGUUGUUCGCCGCAGGACCCAGCGGAGGAAGUCCACCAUCACUGCUCUGCUCUUCGGGGAGGAUGACCUGGAGGCACUCAAGGCCAAGAACAUCAAGCAGACGGAACUGGUGGCUGACCUCCGGGAAGCCAUCCUGCGCGUGGCACGCCACUUCCAGUGCACAGACCCCAAAAACUGCAGCGUGGAGCUGACUCCAGACUAUAGCAUGGAGAGCCACCAGCGGGACCACGAGAACUACGUGGCGUGCUCACGCAGCCACCGGCGCCGAGCCAAGGCCCUGCUGGACUUUGAGCGGCACGACGACGACGAGCUGGGCUUCCGCAAGAACGACAUCAUCACAAUCGUGUCUCAGAAGGACGAGCACUGCUGGGUGGGGGAGCUCAACGGCCUGCGAGGCUGGUUUCCAGCCAAGUUCGUGGAAGUCCUGGAUGAGCGCAGCAAAGAGUACUCCAUCGCGGGGGAUGACUCGGUGACGGAGGGGGUCACAGACCUCGUGCGAGGGACCCUCUGCCCGGCCCUUAAGGCCCUGUUCGAACAUGGACUGAAGAAGCCAUCCCUGCUUGGGGGCGCCUGCCACCCCUGGCUGUUUAUCGAGGAGGCUGCAGGCCGGGAGGUCGAGAGAGACUUUGCCUCCGUGUAUUCCCGUCUGGUGCUCUGUAAGACCUUCAGGUUGGAUGAAGAUGGCAAAGUCCUGACCCCGGAGGAGCUGCUCUACCGGGCUGUGCAGUCUGUGAACGUGACCCACGAUGCAGUGCAUGCACAAAUGGAUGUGAAGCUCCGCUCACUGAUCUGCGUGGGGCUCAACCAGAAGGGCCUGGAGCUGCCCCUGCUCCCCACUCCUGGCCAUGUCCCCAGUGAGCAGGUGCUGCACCUGUGGCUGGAGGUGCUCUGCUCCAGCCUGCCCACCGUGGAGAAGUGGUACCAGCCCUGGUCCUUCCUGCGCAGCCCGGGCUGGGUCCAGAUCAAGUGUGAGCUCCGAGUCCUCUGCUGCUUUGCCUUCAGCCUCUCCCAGGACUGGGAGCUCCCUGCGAAGAGAGAGGCGCAGCAGCCCCUGAAGGAGGGCGUCCGGGACAUGCUGGUGAAGCACCACCUCUUCAGCUGGGAUGUGGACGGGUGACCCCCUCCUCCCCAGCCCAACCUCGGGCCUGCGUCUGAGGUGGCCCAGGACCCCAAGCUGCAGAGCCCAGGGAAGAGCAGCUCCAGAGCCCUGGCCGGGGCCGCGGGAUAUCAAUAUCAGGCUGCCCCACUCCACGUUCCCCAGCACAUCCCAGGUGGUGGGAGCAGAGGGUACCCUGCCCCACCAGGGUCCUUAGGGAUGCUCUAGGCCAAACCACAGUUUGUACCAAAAACCUUGUGAGGAGGUGGGGGAGCCAUGUCUGUGCUCAGGAAGAGGGAAGGGGAUGGGGGUGGCUAGUAGGCUCCUGGCCUCUUUGGUUUAUAAAUAAACUGUGUCUGUCUUUGAGAAAGCACCUACCUGUCUUCUGUGCAGCUAGGGCUGCAGAGCUGUAUUCAGGUCCAAGGUUCUGCCCUUCCUUGAGUGGUCUAGAAGGCACUGCGUGGCCCCUCAGAUGCUGGGACACAACAGACCCGGGACCCAGCUGUGCUACCCACCCCUUCCAUGGACUGAAUAAGAUGGACUAACAGGCC